GUGGGCUCUUGAAACCCGAGCAUGGCACAGCACGGGGCGAUGGGCGCGUUUCGGGCCCUGUGCGGCCUGGCGCUGCUGUGCGCGCUCAGCCUGGGUCAGCGCCCCACCGGGGGUCCCGGGUGCGGCCCUGGGCGCCUCCUGCUUGGGACGGGAACGGACGCGCGCUGCUGCCGGGUUCACACGACGCGCUGCUGCCGCGAUUACCCGGGCGAGGAGUGCUGUUCCGAGUGGGACUGCAUGUGUGUCCAGCCUGAAUUCCACUGCGGAGACCCUUGCUGCACGACCUGCCGGCACCACCCUUGUCCCCCAGGCCAGGGGGUACAGUCCCAGGGGAAAUUCAGUUUUGGCUUCCAGUGUAUCGACUGUGCCUCGGGGACCUUCUCCGGGGGCCACGAAGGCCACUGCAAACCUUGGACAGACUGCACCCAGUUCGGGUUUCUCACUGUGUUCCCUGGGAACAAGACCCACAACGCUGUGUGCGUCCCAGGGUCCCCGCCGGCAGAGCCGCUUGGGUGGCUGACCGUCGUCCUCCUGGCCGUGGCCGCCUGCGUCCUCCUCCUGACCUCGGCCCAGCUUGGACUGCACAUCUGGCAGCUGAGGAGUCAGUGCAUGUGGCCCCGAGGUCUGUCACAGCCUGGUGCGGGGAGGUGGGAGCAUGGCUGCCUGCUGACCGUGGCCCCCCUGCAGAGACCCAGCUGCUGCUGGAGGUGCCGCCGUCGACCGAAGACGCCAGAAGCUGCCAGUUCCCCGAGGAAGAGCGGGGCGAGCGAUCGGCAGAGGAGAAGGGGCGGCUGGGAGACCUGUGGGUGUGAGCCUGGCCGUCCUCCGGGGCCACCGACCGCAGCCAGCCCCUCCCCAGGAGCUCCCCAGGCCGCAGGGGCUCUGCGUUCUGCUCUGGGCCGGGCCCUGCUCCCCUGGCAGCAGAAGUGGGUGCAGGAAGGUGGCAGUGACCAGCGCCCUGGACCAUGCAGUUCGGCGGCCGCGGCUGGGCCCUGCAGGAGGGAGAGAGAGACACAGUCAUGGCCCCCUUCCUCCCUUGCUGGCCCUGAUGGGGUGGGGUCUUAGGACGGGAGGCUGUGUCCGUGGGUGUGCAGUGCCCAGCACGGGACCCGGCUGCAGGGGACCUUCAAUAAACACUUGUCCAGUGA